UUCACAGGGCCUCCGGGAUUUGGCUCUGCCUUCAACUGGGGUGAGACGGCUUAAAUCCUCCUUCACCCAAAGUCCUGGAGGAGGCCUCCACACUCUCUGGCUCUCCCACACUCUCUGGCUCUCUGGUGUGUCUUUGAUCAGCACACCCCAGGGCUCUGACCUGUUUCUGACCACCUGCUAUGUGGAUGAAGAUACAUCUGGGGCCAAGUGAGAAGACCCAGUAGCACCAGGUUUCGCCCCAAAGGAGAGAGGGAGACACGGAGGAUGGUGGAUUUUCCAGGCUACAAUCUGUCUGGUGCAGUCGCCUCCUUCCUAUUCAUCCUGCUGACAAUGAAGCAGUCAGAAGACUUUAGAGUCAUUGGCCCUGCUCAUCCUAUCCUGGCCGGGGUUGGGGAAGAUGCCCUGUUAACCUGCCAGCUACUCCCCAAGAGGACCACAAUGCACGUGGAGGUGAGGUGGUACCGCUCAGAGCCCAGCACACCUGUGUUUGUGCACAGGGAUGGAGUGGAGGUGACUGAGAUGCAGAUGGAGGAGUACAGAGGCUGGGUAGAGUGGAUAGAGAAUGGCAUUGCAAAGGGAAAUGUGGCACUGAAGAUACACAACAUCCAGCCCUCCGACAAUGGACAAUACUGGUGCCAUUUCCAGGAUGGGAACUACUGUGGAGAAACAAGCUUGCUGCUCAAAGUAGCAGGUCUGGGGUCUGCCCCUAGCAUCCACAUGGAGGGACCUGGGGAGAGUGGAGUCCAGCUUGUGUGCACUGCAAGGGGCUGGUUCCCAGAGCCCCAGGUGUAUUGGGAAGACAUCCGGGGAGAGAAGCUGCUGGCCGUGUCUGAGCAUCGCAUCCAAGAUGAAGAUGGCCUGUUCUAUGCGGAAGCCACCCUGGUGGUCAGGAACGCCUCUGCAGAGUCUGUGUCCUGCUUGGUCCACAACCCCGUCCUCACUGAGGAGAAGGGGUCGGUCAUCAGCCUCCCAGAGAAACUCCAGACUGAGCUGGCUUCUUUAAAAGUGAAUGGACCUUCCCAGCCCAUCCUCGUCAGAGUGGGAGAAGAUAUACAGCUAACCUGUUACCUGUCCCCCAAGGCGAAUGCACAGAGCAUGGAGGUGAGGUGGGACCGAUCCCACCGUUACCCUGCUGUGCAUGUGUAUAUGGAUGGGGACCAUGUGGCUGGAGAGCAGAUGGCAGAGUACAGAGGGAGGACUGUGCUGGUGAGUGACGCCAUUGACGAGGGCAGACUGACCCUGCAGAUACUCAGUGCCAGACCUUCGGACGACGGGCAGUACCGCUGCCUUUUUGAAAAAGAUGAUGUCUACCAAGAGGCCAGUUUGGAUCUGAAGGUGGUAGGUCUGGGUUCUUCCCCACUGAUCACUGUGGAGGGGCAAGAAGAUGGAGAAAUGCAGCCGAUGUGCUCUUCAGAUGGGUGGUUCCCACAGCCCCACGUGCCAUGGAGGGACAUGGAAGGAAAGACGAUACCAUCAUCUUCCCAGGCCCUGACUCAAGGCAGCCACGGGCUGUUCCACGUGCAGACAUUGCUAAGGGUCACAAACAUCUCCGCUGUGGACGUCACUUGUUCCAUCAGCAUCCCCUUUUUGGGCGAGGAGAAAAUCGCAACUUUUUCUCUCUCAGAGUCCAGGAUGACGUUUUUGUGGAAAACACUGCUUGUUUGGGGAUUGCUUCUUGCUGUGGCUGUAGGCCUGCCCAGGAAGAGGAGCUGAAAAGAGUGAAUGUGACAUUGGCUUCAAACACAGCUCACCUGAGACUGAUUUCUUCUGAACAAAACAAGCGUGUGAUCCAUGGACAUUCAGGCAGCCAGAUAUCCCACAGAGAUCUGACUAUCUGCUCUAUGGGCCAGAGGGAACUCCUGUCAGGGAGCUGGUACUGAGAGGUGGAGACUGGGAACAGGGCGCGAUGGGUCCCGGAGGUUGCCAAGCACAUGUUGCAAAGAAAGAGUCAUCUCUGUGUCACCUGACAGUGAGUUUUAGGCAAUGGAUUGCAAAAGAAAUGAGUUCUGGGCCAUCCCCUCUCUUCCAAGCCCCAUACCCUUGAAGGUGGCCCCUGAACAAGUCAGAAUCCCCCUGACCGUGCCUCUGAAUACCUCUCCUCUUAUAACAUGAUUGGCAAGUGCCCUAUCUACACCUUCCCCAAAACUUCCUUCUCUGGGACUCUGCACCCCGCUUCAUUCUUUGGUUCCCUAAUGUAGGUUCUCUGGACAUUUUUUCUGUACCC